AUCCAAGGCGCAAGAUGGCGCUGCUUUUUGCACGUUCUUUGCGCUUGUGCCGCUGGGGAGCCAAACGAUUGGGAGUUGCCUCCACAGAGGCCCAGAGAGGCGUCAGUUUCAAACUGGAAGAAAAAACCGCCCACAGCAGCCUGGCACUCUUCAGAGAUGAUACGGGUGUCAAAUAUGGCUUGGUGGGAUUGGAGCCCACCAAGGUGGCCUUGAAUGUGGAGCGCUUCCGGGAGUGGGCAGUGGUGCUGGCAGACACAGCGGUCACCAGUGGCAGACACUACUGGGAAGUGACAGUGAAGCGCUCCCAGCAGUUCCGGAUAGGAGUGGCAGAUGUGGACAUGUCCCGGGAUAGCUGCAUUGGUGUUGAUGAUCGUUCCUGGGUGUUCACCUAUGCCCAGCGCAAGUGGUACACCAUGUUGGCCAACGAGAAAGCCCCAGUUGAGGGUAUUGGGCAGCCAGAGAAGGUGGGGCUGUUGCUGGAGUAUGAGGCCCAGAAGCUGAGCCUGGUGGAUGUGAGCCAGGUCUCUGUGGUUCACACGCUACAGACAGAUUUCCGGGGUCCAGUGGUGCCUGCCUUUGCUCUCUGGGAUGGGGAGCUGCUGACCCAUUCAGGGCUUGAGGUGCCCGAGGGCCUCUAGUAUGUCCAUUACUGGAGUCCCUAAUCACGCCUUUGGCCAGCCUCCUUUUGAAAGUGUCCGAAGCCUUUUUACUUUGCCUCAAGCAACCUCUAGCUCCCACAAUUCAGUGUUGGGUCCUCUGUGCAAUAUCAUGAUCAUCUUCCUCAUCCCCUACCUUGUGAAAGCUAGGCAUACAGCCAAACCCUCCUUUUCCCCACCCACCAACUACUGCCAAUUUCCUAGGCUACCAUGGGUGUAUCUUCCUUGACCUGCUUCCUUCAGUCCCUCUGCCUCCCUUUGCCCAGGCCUUUCUCAGACUGUAUUCCAUCCUGGGGUCUUAUCAUUCAGCUUUGUUUGAAUUUAUUAAUCACCAUGAUACCUCUCCCUCCCUUUGUCCACAUGUAACUUGUUCUUGGGGCUCUACCAGAUGGCUGAAGAGUAAAUCCUUUCUACCUCUGGCUGAAGGAGUGGUGCAGUCAAUGACUUGGCCCUUUUUCUACAGCACAUUUAGAGUUUGGGCUCUGGCUCCCUCAGUAAGUGCUUUAUUAACUCAGUGUGUCAAAAUGAAAACAGAGCCCUCCUUCCCCAGUAGCUCAGUGCCACAGACCUUCAGCCCCACACAGCUGUAGCUAUCCUUACCCUGAGUCCAUCUACCUUAAAUCUGUACCUCUGACACCCAGCCAGUCUGUCAUAAUCAUUAUCCCAGUUAUAACCUUGACCAAAGGGGAAGAGAGACACUUGGGGGAUAUCUAGGGGAUGAGUGCUAGAAACUAUUUAUUUAUUUUUGAGACAGAGUCUCACUCUGUCACCCAGGCUGGAGUGCAGUGGCAUGAUCUUGGCUCACUGCAAACUCUGCCUUUUGGGUUCAAGCGACUCUCGUGCCUCAGCCUCCUGAGUAGCUAGGAUUACAGGUGUGUGCCACCAUGCCCGUCUCAUUUUUAUAUUUUUAGUAGAGAUGGGGUUUUGCCAUAUUGGCCAGGCUGGUCUCGAACUCCUGGCCUCAUGUGAUCAGCCCACCUUGGCCUCCCAAAGUGCUGGGAUUUCAGGCGUGAGCCACCACACCCGGCCAAAACUGUUUAUUCUUGAGAAGUUCCAUCUUCAUUUCUGCCACAGUUGGAACUUCCCGAGGAAGGAAGGAGGCCUGAGGUUUUGCACAAUCUGUUUCAGAGCCUGUUUAGACUCAAACCUAUGCUUCCCUUGGCAGCAGAAUACACUUAACCUAAAGCAGUAUUUGGAGUUGAGAAAAACCUGGUGGGGUAAGUGAAUAUGUACUGUUUGGUAGGGUAGGUAGAGAAGCUGUGCUUUGACCCUGUGAUUCCAUCUUUUUCUACCUUCUAUGAUGGUGAUGAAGCUAGAUACCCCUAGGGAAGAAAGAAGGACUGGGUUUAGCAAAAAUGAUUUGGUAAUUAAAGUUUAUUUGAACACAAAAUACUUUCUCUGUCUAUAAAAUUGGCUGUUAGCAGUAGCAGCAGCAUGUCCUGGCCAAGGGGAGUAGAUUUCUCCAGACUACUAAAGCCAUGUAUAUAGCCAUUCCCACUUCCCAUAUUCUGUGGAUAUGUACAUGUGCAUGGUAGCUAGAGUCCCUCCACCAGAGUAUCUCUCUCAUGAUGGUUUCUUCAGGGAGAGGAAGAGGAGACCUGGGUGAAGAGCUGGGAUGGUUUUGAGUGGGGCAAGCCAUUAGGCUGUACCUUGAAGCCCAGUCUCUCUGGAUAGCUGUACUGCAGGUGUCCUCUGAGGCCCUUCUCUGUACUCUGUCUGCUGAGGGAAUGGGGUAUUUUGACUCCCAUAGAAAGCACUAGCCUAAGUCACCAAAUGACUGCUUGGUCCCCACUGAAGCAGUGUAGCUCUCCAUAGUAUUUUUGGUGGUUAUGGAUUACAUGUGUGGCCAGCUCAUGCUUUUUCUUGAGCAGGGGCUGUCCAUGACCUGUGCUCAUACCAUGCUUUCUAAGUUCUCUUUGGACAGGGCCUCAGCUGCUGCCUCAGCCUGAGUUUCAGAGAGUGUGUAGGAGUCCUGGUAAUCUUGAAGCAGUUUGACCACCUCCAGAUGGUUGAACUGCACAGCAUCAUCCAGGGGAAUGUUGCCCCACCUGAGAGGAAUAAUGAUAUGAUCAGGCAAAGGAGACGUGGAGAGUGGUGGUUGUAUAUAUUUGCAUGGUGGCUGGAGGGUAGGUGGAGAAGCUGUGCCCACCCUCCUCCACUUUUAGCCUAUUCCUCACCUGUCCUUGGCAAAAGGAUUCACUUUGCAAGCCUCGAUCAGGAAUUUAACAACUUCGAUGUGUCCUAGGAAUAUGGGCAGAAGGAAAAUGAGAAGGCGCAGGUCUUGAACCCUUUGGUGCAGACACUUAGCCACUGAAGUCUUUACCAAGAGGGGAGGGGAAAAGGCCUCUUCCCAUUUUGUACCCUGCAGCACUCAGUCAUAGUCUAGCUGCAAACCGAAGGGUGUCUAGAUAAAACUAGUUGCUGCCCCUAUAACCUUGAGGGCACAUAUAAUGAAGGUACUUUUGGUGAAAAAGAAAGGGUCUUAUGAUUACCCUCCUCCUCCCCUCCUUAACCCUUCAGUACCUUCAGCUGCAGCAACAUGCAGAGCUGUGCGCGAGUCAUAGUCUUUCUGUUCCAUAUCCAUGGCUGACAAGGCAAACCUGAGGGUAGUGGGAAAGCAGCUAGAGUUGCCUAGAUCAGACUGGAAUCACAGGUGUUCUUUGUGAACUGGUGUCAGACUGGAUGAGUUUCAGAGAAAGUGAAACAGCCUAUAGCCAGAUUUGUUGGCUCUGAAUAAUCUUUUUUCCAUAUCCAGAUGAGACUGUUAUACUCAUAUUAGAGAGAUGGGAAUGUGAUCCUUCCAGAAAUAUCACUCACUGCCUACCUGUGGUAAGUGCCCAUUUGAGGCAGGGUACCUACUUCCUAGGACACUGCUCUUAACACUCAAUAACAAUGGCUAACAUUAAUUAUCAUAGAGCAGACAGUUUACUUUUUUUAAAAAAAAUCUCCUUUUUUAAAAAAAUUUCAUUUAAAUGCAAUCUAUAUCCAUUCUAAUUCCAAAGCUGAAGCACUUAACUAUUUUGUUACGCUGCCUCCUAGUAAAAUCUCUGACCAGGAGUAUUUUAUUGUGUAUAUUUGGUCACAGUAGCAUUACCUUCGAAGAGCUGAGACAUCGCCACUAUAGGCAGCAAAUAACAGGUUGACCACAGUCUUGUUCUGGAACACAAAUCAUACCCACAUGACAUUAAUUGAACUCACCUAUGCCAGCUGUGCCCUGUGACCCUCCUCCAUGGAUGCUUAGUCCAAGGGUAUUGCUGAAGUGUUAUGGAAUGUGCUACUCUGAAAUAUUCUUUUUUUUUUUUUUUUUUUUGAGACGGAGUCUCGCUCUGUCGUUCAGGCUGAAGUGUAGUGGCGCGCGGUCUUGGCUCACUGCAACCUCUGCCUCCCGGUUUCAAGCGAUUCUCCUGCCUCAGCCUCCCAAGUAGCUGGGACCACAGGCGCGUGCCACCACGUCUGGCUAAUUUUUUGUAUUUUCAAUAGAGACCAGGUUUCACCGUGUUAGCCAGGAUGGUCUUGAUCUCCUGACCUUGUGAUCCGCCCGCCUUGGCCUCUCAAAGUGCAGGGAUUACAGGCGUGAGCCACCGCACCUGGCCUUUGAAAUAUUCUUACAAGCCACCUGGAGUUUUCCUUACCCGAAUUUCUGCCCCUUCACGCCGUGGGUCUAACUUCCGAGCACAGUGCCUCAGGUUGUCAUAGUUGUGGAAAUUGAAGAGAGACACCAACUUCUAGAAUUGUAAGCCAAAUAUAUUGUUUAUUUACUCCUUACACUUAGUAGGAGCUCAAAAUUGCUUUAUUAUAGUAAAAGUGGUACCAUUAAACAAAUUUAUUGCUUCAAAAAUAGUAAGUACUAUAUGCAAAGCAUCUCACCUGGCAGAAGCUGGUCCCCCUAUGGCUGUUCCCCAGCUUGUCCAAUGGGGGUGACAGGCACAUCAUUCCCAUGACAUUGGGUACCACCAGGAGGAUGGCUCCUGAUACAGCUGACUUGGCUGGCAGGCCCACCUGGGGAACAGAACUGAAGCUGAGGAUAAAGUGGGUGUGCCCCAAAUCAGAAAAUAAACAAGUUAGGCUGUACUCUUAACAAGUUUACAAAUGACUGCAUGACCACAAUCCACCUCAACCUUUUGGCUUGUUAAUUAGCUUCUUUUAUUACUCCUGUCCUUUCCUUCCCUUAAAUUCAUUGAUUCAGCUAGAAAAUAUUUUUUGAAAUACUUACAGCAUUCUGUGCUAGAUGCUGUGCUAGAACUAGGAACUUCCAUUCUGGUGUUAGGAGAUAGGUAAUAAACAGGUAAAUAAAUAGACACGUAAUGUUUAAAGUAAUUGUGAUAAAUAGUGAGAAGUAGGGUGCUGUAAAUAGAGGUAGAGGGGGGCCACAUGAGAUAGGGUGGUCAGAAAAGUCUUUCUUUGGAAAUGACAUCUAAGCUGAGACCCCAAGGAGAAGAGCCAGCAAUGUGAAGCACAAUUCAGGAGCUGCAACACCUCUGGUUGUUUUUCUUUUUCUUUUUUUCUUUUUUUUUGAGAUGGAGUUUUGCUCUUGUUGCCCAGGCUACAGUGCAAUGGCACAAUCUCGGCUCAGUGCAACCUCUGCCUCCCAGGUUCAAGCACUUCUGCCUCAGCCUCCCAAGUAGCUGGGAUUACAGGUGCACACCACCACCCCCGGCUAAUUUUUUGUAUUUAGUAGAGAUGGGGUUUCACCAUGUAGGUCAGGCUGGUCUCGAACUCCUGACCUCAGGUGAUCCACCUGCCUCGGCCUCCCAAAGACAUCUCUUUAUAUAUUCGAGGAACUUGGUGUUUUUGAGAAACUCGUCUAAGGAGUCUCAACCUAAUUGCCUUCCUGGAAGUUAGUGAAUGAGAGGCAGGAACAAGCUUCCACCUCUAUCUUGAGAGAGUCAGUGUUCUCUCUUCUUAGCACUGGGCUCAUGACAGAUGGAUAGCAGAGCCAGAAACUCACGUGGAAGGCAAACUGGCCAGAGAAGUCAUACAUGCCGCAGGAAUGCAUGAGGCUGAGGGUGUUGCGCACUGCUUCAGCACUCAGCACACUCUCGCCUGUGAUGGGGCAGAUCCCACCGUUGGCGAGGGUGGCUGCCAUGACACUGCCUGAUUCACAAGUGACCUCCACAGAACACAGCUAUGAAAACAAAGAAUAGGUGAAGAUGUGACGUGAACCUGCACAUGGGACCCUCGGGUGUAGGGAAAGGGCAAGGGCAAGGACAGUCUGUCCUGUUCCCUCGGCCCUGAGCAGUGUUUUCUUACCUGGAAGUAGAGAUCAAGGGCAGCCAUCAUGUCCACCCCCUUAGGAAAGCACUGCAAGGAAGAGAGGGGAGAGCAUUUCUCUUCAGGACAUCAGCCCUUUCACACUGUCAGGGUCUCAGCUGAAGCCCCCAACCCCUACUGCCCUUCCACUAGCAGCAGAAUUCCCAGGGACUUUCUCUUCCGGCCUCUUCUGGUUACCUUCUUUUCCUUGAGAUAAUAGCCGAUGGCAUAAUUCCGAUCCCCUGUUUCCUUCUCUGACUGGAAUCUGAAGCAAACACCCAAUUUAGUACUUGAAGUUGGAGGAGUGGGUGUUGGGAGAAGGGGAAAAAUUACCUUCCCUGGAGAGACAGAACUACAUCACACCACAAACUAAAUGAACCCCUUUAUAACUUCUCACAGUAAUAUUAGAGGAAAUUUCUGAACCUGAGCAAACACUCAGCAUAGUUUUGUUAUAAAGUAAACCCAAACCAAACACCCCAAACUGUCUAGUCAUCUAGGAAAACUGGUGAAGUUUUUGGCUUUGAAAGUCUUGGCAAGAAAGGGCUUAGGCACAAACCAUCACACUGCCUCUCUCAUUAUGUACUAAUUAGAAAUGGAACAAAUUAUUUUACAAGAUAAACAAAUGUUUAUGAAGGGACUCAGAGGAAGCUGGAGGGCCAAAGUUCCCCUGGGAUUUCUUCCUCCUAAGAUUCUCUCUCCCCCAUUCCUCUUGUCCCCAUCCUAAGUACACACACAUACACCACAAUGCUUUCAGUCAGUCCUCUGAGUAGGGACUUACGUGGCAUUGCUGAAACCCAUGUAUUCAUUCCCAGCCAUUUUGUUGAGAUACUGCAACACCUGGAAGAGAAAAAGGGACAUUGAGGCUCCACUUGGUUAAGAAGCUCUAUUAAUACCUCACAGGUUGACUAGCCCUUCUGAACUCAGGUCUUGUCAAGAGGCUUUCCUCUCUGAGGCCAGCAGAUUUCCACAUUUCUGGAAAUAAGGCUUCUAGUAUGGGCUGGUGCACCUGGUAGUGGGGUUAGAGAGCCACUGGGGCAGCUGGAGAGGACAGCAUGCCAUGGCGAAAUGCAGCCAGGGGCUAAGUAGCAAGGGAACUUACAAAAUCAAACUUCUCUGCUUUGUUACAGUCCAUCUGCAGAGAAAGAGAGAGAUGUCAGCAUUCUAAGUGUAGGAGGAUGACAGAGGGAAGGGUCAGAAGGAUCUAGUGGAGUUCUAGUGUUAGUCUGGUCCUGCUGCUGCAAAUGUGUUCAAUUUUAUAAUGGCCCUUUUUUUAUCCUUCUGAAAACACCGCACUUCCAUUGGCUCCUCUCUUUCUCUUUCUUUUUUUUGAGACAGUCUUGCUUUGUCACCCUUGUCACCCAGGCUGGAGUGCAGUGGCACGAUCAUGGCUCACUGCAGCUUUGACCUCCCAGGCUCAAGCGAUCCUCCCACUUCAGCCUCCAAGUAGCUCGGAUUACAGGCAUGAGCCAGCUUGCUGGGCCAUCCCACUUCCAUUCUCAAUCCAAACCCUCAUCCCUGACUCCCACGUUCAUUUUCCUGACUCGAAUCCUGUCUCCUAGCCCCACCCUAUCCCUGAUCUCCAUCCCCAUUCCUUACACCCCAUGCUGGAGCUUUACUCCAUCCCAUUGGCCAGCAUGAUGGUUCAUGCCUGUAAUCUCAGCAAUUUGGGGGGCUGAGGCAGGAGGAUCGCUUGAGACCAGGGGUUUGAGACCAGCCUAGGCAACAUAGGAGAGACCCUGCCUCAAUUUUUUUUUUUUUUUUUUUUUGAGAUGGAGUCUUGCUCUGUCGCCCAGGCUGGAGUGCAGUGGCAGGAUCUCGGCUCAACUGCAAGCUCCGCCUCCCGGGUUCAUACCAUUCUCCUGCCUUAGCCUCCCGAGCAGCUGGGACCACAGGUGCCCACCACCAAGCCUGGCUAAUUUUUUGUAUUUUUAGUAGAGACGGGGUUUCACCGUGCUAGCCAGGAUGGUCUCGAUCUCCUGACCUCGUGAUUUGCCCACCUCGGCCUCCCAAAGUGUUGGGAUUACAGGCGUGAGCCACCGCGCCUGGCCUCUAUAUUUUUUAAAAAAGGUCCUACUUAGAUGGGAAUGGGAUGAGGCAGGUCCCAGAUACAGGUUUGUAGAUGGAGCCAUCACAGAACAAGGGGAGAGACUCAGCCUCUUUUCCUCACCCAGACUCAUUGCUUACUCAUGUGUCAACUACAGAGUCAAUACCACAGGGACUCUGAUACCUGAGUCCCUGAGGGGAGGAUUCCUAACACCACCUUCCCCAGGAGGGGCUGUGAUUGGCUCCAGGGUGUUGCUGCCCAGCUGCUCCCAGGUUCUUGCUCAAGCCCUGGGAGACCUACAGCUGAUGGGCUAGUCUGACACCCUGUUCAAGGCCAACUCACAGUUCCAGGUGACGUGAAUAACUGCCCUGGCCUGGCCAUUCACCCUUGCCUGCAGGUGUCCCACACCCAGAAGUGGCCAAUCAGUGCCCAAUAGUGCUGUCCUCCCCUUGUCUCUGGCAUUUGGCCCUUGGUCCUAGGCAGGGGUCAGGACCUGCUCACUUCUCUAAGGGUCAGAAAGCUCUAGGCUCUAGACUCAUGGGUGGGGGCAGGGAACAGUACUGAGUGGGGAUGACGGAGGUGGUGCAGUCUCUUAUACUGACAUUGUCAGCAUAACAUGUGGGUCCCUGCUGUGCCUCAUGUGCCUUCUGGGGACCCUCAAAGGAAUCAGAGCCCCACCAGUCUCCCUGGAGAGCUGAACAAAUAUGAGGGAUACAGGAACACAGGAGCUUAGAGGAUAAUACCUAUCAGAAGGUUAAGGUGGCACUGACCUUGAUCAGGGAGCUGACAACAAUGGCACCAGCAUUGACCAUGGGGUUAUGGGGGAUUCCUGGGGAAAUACAAACCACCAAGAGUCUUAGCCACUGAACAAAGCCUCCCUGACAGCCCGCUCACUUUGUGGGUUAGACAAGAAAGACUGCUAGGGAGAAAGGCAUGACAGGGCUAAUCAGGAAGGGCAGAGAAACAAAAAAGGCUGGGAGAUGGGGUGGGGAUAAGGAGAAGGGGACAGCUGUAAGUACGGUCUGAGCCUUGGUAGUGCUCACCUUCCUCAUUGAGGGAGAGCUUGUUGUAGCGCAGGCCACUUGGCUCUUUGCCCACAAACUUGUGCACGUAGUCAGUGCCUAGGGUGCUUAUGGAGAUGGCAUAGGUGAGGGGCUUCACACAGGACUGCAGGCAGAAGGGGAUCUUUGUGUGGCCCACAGAGUGCCUGGAGGCAGACAGAUGCCAUGAAAGGGGUUGGCCUGUGUUCGGCACCUGUGCCCUGCCUCCCCUUCCUCUUGCCCAGCAUCUCACCGUUGACCAUCCACAGUGCACAGGGAGACACCCCACAGGUCUGGGUUUGACUUGGCCAGCUGAGGGAUGUAGGCUGCCACCUGGACAUGAGUGGGUAGAGAAAAGGGAGAUGGAUGUGGAGAAGAGGAACAGAGUUGAGGUUGAGGGUCAAGAGAAUCUUUUAGAUAAAAGCUAAAAUUCUGUCUUCUAUAGGGCAGAGGGGUUCCCUCCUGCCUGUUGCUCCCAGAAAUGCCCGAGCCUUAAGUCCUAGAAGGCCAUAUCUUUGUGUAUCCGCAAUCCUGUAGAGAUAGCAGUAAAGCCAAUGGAAGUUAAAAAAGGAGAAUUCUGAGGCAACCUUCCCCUUUUGGUUCUUAGGCUCAGUUACCCUAUAAAUCCCUUUGAAGGCUCUAUUCGAUCUUGAUUCCCUCACCUGCUCUAGGAAUCGUGUAUAGAAACACAUGAAGCCAUGUCACCAUUUACAGAAGUUCUGCUUCUCAUCUCUCAUUCAUAGGACUCCCAGCCCCAGGAAAUCUCUGAGAAGCGAGGUAUAUCUAGGUGUGGUGGCUCAUGCCUGUAAUCCCAGCACUUUGGGAGGCCGAGGUGGGUGGAUCACUUGAGAUCAGGAGUUCGAGACCAGCCUGGCCAAUAUGGCAAAACCCCAUCUCUACUAAAAAUACAAAAAUUAGUCGGGCAUGGUGGUGUAUGCCAGCUACUCGGGAGGCUGAGACAGGAGAAUCGCUUGAACCUGGGAGGUGGAGGUUGCAGUGAGCUGAGAUUGCACCAUUGCACUCCAGCCCGGGUGACAGAGCAAAACUCUGUCUCAGGAAAAAAAAAAAAAAAAAAAAUCUGGCCCAGGUCCCUGACCCCUCCCUUAGUCCCCUGACUCUCACUUUGCCUCCAGUGAGCUCUUUGACAUCCUCAAAGAUGCGAUCCACAUGGCCCGUGAACUCCUCAAAAUCAGGAAUGACAAACUUCUUUCGGAAUGCCUGGGUCAGGAGCACAAUGUUGCUGCUCACACACCUGGAUCCCAGACACGAUUGGAUUAGGGGGCUAGAGAAAUGCAGCUGGGACUCACUCUGGAGCCACGGAAAUUGGGAAUAAAGAAGGUUGAGUGGUCUUCAGGUUUGGGAUCAACAGCUCUGUUACCUUUGGCAAAUCAGUUUACCUUUCUAGGUCUUAGUUUCCGUACCUCUAAAAUGAGGGGUUUUAAUGAUGUGGAAAGACACUAUGUCUUGGGAUAUGAGAAAAAAAAUAAAUACCAGAAUAAUAUGUAUGUAUGUUACCUUGAUAUUUAAAAAAUCCUAAAUCAUAAAAGUAUAUUUAUAUAUAUUCAUGUAUGUAUGUCAGUACAUAGGACAUUAUCUAGAAGAUACCCACUAAUCUGCUAAUAUUUACUUCUGGGAAAAGAGGACAGGGAUUGAGUAGGGAGGGAAAGGAGAACAUGUAUUUCUAUAUUGUUUGAACUCUUAUGAUGAGUAUUCAUGUAUAACUUAUGUAAUAAGUAAUAAAAUAAAAUGAGGAAUUGAACUAUACAAUUCCCAAAUUCC